GAGCUGAGAUCGCGCCAUUGCACUCCAGCCUGAACAACAAGAAUGAAACUCCGUCUCAAAAAAGAAAAAUUUGCAAAGGUGAGGGUCCAUCCUCAUUGCUAGGGUGCCCUUUGCCCUCUGCCCUUUGCCCUUCCCCUGCCCCAACUCUUCUGUUUUUCAGCAGGAAGAGGGUGGGCUGGGCUCAAGCAGGUGGUGGCAAGUGGCUGACCUGCAGGUGGGCUCUGUGUUUGCACCAGCUGGGCUGUUAGGAGAGGCAGGCGUGAGACGACCCCAGCUGGGGGGUGUUGAACUUGGCACUAUGGGGUGAGGAUUAACCACAGCAGCCCAGGCUACUUCUCAGUUCCCUUAUCACCUCCUGAACCCCACCCCCCCAGCAAUGAAUGUUAAUAAACCCCACCCUUCUUCCCUCCCCCUUUCCCCGAGCUCACUCCAGUCAAGGGAGAGAGUCUGACAGUUUAGGUCAACUGAGGCUAAGCCACAAAAAGGGCCCCUGCCCCCAUUCUUGUGGCACUUGAUGCGUUUCUGUGAGUCCUUUAUCUCAGCUGACGUGGAUGGCGGUGGUUUUGACAGUAUCCCUGCUGGUAGCCAUUUCCUUUUUAUAAACUGGGACCCUGAAACCAGAGAAGUGAAGGGACUUGCCACAGGUCACACAGCGUAUAAGGACCAGGGCAAAGGGGCGGGGAUAAAAUCAAGGGCUCCAUGCUGCCUCCCCACUUGGGGCCCACCACUGGCUUCCCCAUGGGCGUAAAGGAGCAAACCAAGUUAGAAGGCCAGGCCUGCAGGUGCCCAACAGGAAGGGACAAGGAGCCACAGCUGUCUUGCCUGUGACACAGGCCAUCCAGCCAUGCCCAGAGCUAACCCCCUGGCUAAGCCCCGAGGCCCAGCUUGACUGCUGGCAUCUGUUACCAUGGAGACCCAGGCUGGCCUGAGGGCUGGGCCAGUGAUGGCAGGCCCUGUCCCCAUGGAUAGAAACAGGUGCUUGGGCUCAGAGGCCUUGAGUGGCUCCCACUGUCCCCAUGGCCAGUGAGUCCCGACAGCAUAAAUUGGAACCGUUACCCACCUUUCGCCCCCCAGCUGACACCUCCACCAACCCAAGGCCUGAGCUGUCCCCUCCACGUGUCUGUGCUCUCUUUAAUGCCCUGCCUGGGGGCUGGGAGUGGUGAGGAUGUGGAUGUGAGGUUGAAGGUUUCUCAGGGAAUGAGCCAGAGCUGCCAGAAGAGGCAGAGUGUAACCCAGACUGCAGAUGAUGGGAAGAACGCGGAACAGAAGUGACCUGAAGGAUCCGCAGGGGGAAAGCAGAGAGGUGGGCACGCGGGCACCUGGUACCUUGUCCCAGCCAUGCCACCAGCUAGCUGUGAGGCUUUGGGCGAGUCCCUUGCCCUCUCUGGCUCUCAUCCAAGGAAUGAGGAAGUUGGAACAAAUGAUGAAUCCCUAAGACCCCUUCUAGGUUUGACAUUCUUUGAGUUGCAUUCCAAAACCCUGGACUCCCCCAGGUAAGCAAGGCCAGGGCUUGCCCCAUCCUCCCCACACAAGCUCAGGCAGCACCCACUCCUGGGCUGGGUUCCCGAGGAAGAGCCUGCGGAGAGGAGACCCCGGAGCUGCCUGCACUGGUCAGUGCAUGGGGGCAGGGGUGGCAGACCACUUUGUGGAUUGAUGGAGCUCAGGAAGGUGAGAAGGGACCCACAGGUGAGAGUUUCGCUCCCCUGGUCAUCUCUUUAGGUAAAUAAAUCCACAUCCGCCACUUCCCCUUCCCUUCCCACCCUGGGGGCGCUGAGAACUCCAGGGAGCCCAGAGCUGAGGCCUGAGCUCUGCUUGCUCACACUGGGUCUUCCCUCAGAGACCCCCAAGCCCUCCUAUCUUCUGCAGUCACCGUCAUCCACUUUUCUGUAGGGAGGGAACAGCAUGGAGCUCUCUGUUCACCGGUCUCCAGGACCUCGGAUUCCACCUUUAAUCCUGAAAACCCAGGAAGGCUUCUGUAUCCCUACAAUGAAGCAGCUGCUGAUUCUCUGCUGUCAAACUCAGGGGGAGAAUCACCCGUCUCCUAAUUUUAACCAGUACGUGAGGGACCAGGGCGCCAUGACCGACCAGCUGAGCAGGCGGCAGAUCCGCGAGUACCAACUCUACAGCAGGACCAGUGGCAAGCACGUGCAGGUCACCGGGCGUCGCAUCUCCGCCACCGCCGAGGACGGCAACAAGUUUGCCAAGCUCAUAGUGGAGACGGACACGUUUGGCAGCCGGGUUCGCAUCAAAGGGGCUGAGAGUGAGAAGUACAUCUGUAUGAACAAGAGGGGCAAGCUCAUCGGGAAGCCCAGCGGGAAGAGCAAAGACUGCGUGUUCACGGAGAUCGUGCUGGAGAACAACUAUACGGCCUUCCAGAACGCCCGGCACGAGGGCUGGUUCAUGGCCUUCACGCGGCAGGGGCGGCCCCGCCAGGCUUCCCGCAGCCGCCAGAACCAGCGCGAGGCCCACUUCAUCAAGCGCCUCUACCAAGGCCAGCUGCCCUUCCCCAACCACGCCGAGAAGCAGAAGCAGUUCGAGUUUGUGGGCUCCGCCCCCACCCGCCGGACCAAGCGCACACGGCGGCCCCAGCCCCUCACGUAGUCUGGGAGGCAGGGGGCAGCAGCCCCUGGGCCGCCUCCCCACCCCUUUCCCUUCUUAAUCCAAGGACUGGGCUGGGGUGGCGGGAGGGGAGCCAGAUCCCCGAGGGAGGACCCUGAGGGCCGCGAAGCAUCCGAGCCCCCAGCUGGGAAGGGGCAGGCCGGUGCCCCAGGGGCGGCUGGCACAGUGCCCCCUUCCCGGACGGGUGGCAGGCCCUGGAGAGGAACUGAGUGUCACCCUGAUCUCAGGCCACCAGCCUCUGCCGGCCUCCCAGCCGGGCUCCUGAAGCCCGCUGAAAGGUCAGCGACUGAAGGCCUUGCAGACAACCGUCUGGAGGUGGCUGUCCUCAAAAUCUGCUUCUCGGAUCUCCCUCAGUCUGCCCCCAGCCCCCAAACUCCUCCUGGCUAGACUGUAGGAAGGGACUUUUGUUUGUUUGUUUGUUUCAGGAAAAAAGAAAGGGAGAGAGAGGAAAAUAGAGGGUUGUCCACUCCUCACAUUCCACGACCCAGGCCUGCACCCCACCCCCAACUCCCAGCCCCGGAAUAAAACCAUUUUCCUGCAAA